GAGAGUCCUUCUAGCGGCGCCGGUGAGUCCGCGUGUGGAAGUCUGUGAGGCGCAGAGGUGGGGCAGGCCGUCUGGCUAGCUAGGCGGCUGGGAGCGUUUUCGUGGCGGGGAACGGAGGUUGAAUUGCCCUGCCUGGGCUCAUAGGGAAGGAGGAUGUGAAGGAGCUUGUGAAGGCAGAGGAAGGUAACUUUCGUCUGGGGAGCCGCAGAGUAGGGAGGGAAGCUGCAGGCCGUCUCUCCCUAAGUAAAAGCGCGACUUUUAGAAAUGAUGGUUCAGGGUUCGAGUUUGUGACCCGCUUGAGAAAGUGACCAACCUCUGAGCCUGAAUCCCAUACCUGAAAAACAAGGACAGUAAUCACCCUUGCCAGUUUCACAUAGCUUGGCUGGAGUGCAGUGGCACAACCUUGGCUCGCUCCAGUGUCUACCUGCCAGGUUCAAGUGAUUCUCCUGCCUCAGCCUCCCGAGUAGCUGGGAUUACAGAUUAUUGAAUAAUAAAAUACAGUUUUGAAAAAAAUGGAUGAAGAACCUGAAAGAACUAAGCGAUGGGAAGGAGGCUAUGAAAGAACAUGGGAGAUUCUUAAAGAAGAUGAAUCUGGAUCACUUAAAGCUACAAUAGAAGACAUUCUAUUCAAGGCAAAGAGAAAAAGAGUAUUUGAGCACCAUGGACAAGUUCGACUUGGAAUGAUGCGCCACCUUUAUGUGGUAGUAGAUGGAUCAAGAACAAUGGAAGACCAAGAUUUAAAGCCUAAUAGACUGACGUGUACUUUAAAGUUGUUGGAAUACUUUGUAGAGGAAUAUUUUGAUCAAAAUCCUAUUAGUCAGAUUGGAAUAAUUGUAACUAAGAGUAAAAGAGCUGAAAAAUUGACUGAACUUUCAGGAAACCCAAGAAAACAUAUAACGUCUUUGAAGAAAGCUGUGGAUAUGACCUGCCAUGGAGAGCCAUCUCUUUAUAAUUCCCUAAGCAUAGCUAUGCAGACUCUAAAACACAUGCCUGGACAUACAAGUCGAGAAGUACUAAUCAUCUUUAGCAGCCUUACAACUUGCGAUCCAUCUAAUAUUUAUGAUCUAAUCAAGACCCUAAAGGCAGCUAAAAUUAGAGUAUCUGUUAUUGGAUUGUCUGCAGAAGUUCGCGUUUGCACUGUACUUGCUCGUGAAACUGGUGGCACGUACCAUGUUAUUUUAGAUGAAAGCCAUUACAAAGAGUUGCUCACACAUCAUGUUAGUCCUCCUCCUGCUAGCUCAAGUUCUGAAUGCUCACUUAUUCGUAUGGGAUUUCCUCAGCACACCAUUGCUUCUUUAUCUGACCAGGAUGCAAAACCCUCUUUCAGCAUGGCGCAUUUGGAUGGCAAUACUGAGCCAGGGCUUACAUUAGGAGGCUAUUUCUGCCCACAGUGUCGGGCAAAGUACUGUGAGCUACCUGUUGAGUGUAAAAUCUGUGGUCUUACUUUGGUGUCUGCUCCCCACUUGGCACGGUCUUACCAUCAUUUGUUUCCUUUGGAUGCUUUUCAAGAAAUUCCCCUAGAAGAAUAUAAUGGAGAAAGAUUUUGUUAUGGAUGUCAGGGGGAAUUGAAAGACCAACAUGUUUAUGUUUGUGCUGUGUGCCAAAAUGUUUUCUGUGUGGACUGUGAUGUUUUUGUUCAUGAUUCUCUACACUGUUGCCCUGGCUGUAUUCAUAAGAUUCCAGCUCCUUCAGGUGUUUGAUUCCAGCAUGUAGUAUACAUUGUAUGUGUUAAAAAGAAAUUUGCAACUGUGAAUAAAAGGACUUCUUUAGAAGAAGCUUCAUUUAAAACAUGAAAGGAUAAUCUGACUUAAGAAACUUUUUGCUAAGAAAAGGUAAUAUUUUAUUAAAUUUUAAAUUUGUGUUGUCACAGAAAUACCUGAAAUUCAGUAGUACUUCAUUCAAUUAAUUUUGUUUUCUAUUAUUUUGAGUUAUACUGUUUUCAAAGUCAUUAUGCAGUAUGUAUAAACUUAUAAGAAUUAAAUUGAUGUGAUAAUUUUAUGUUUUUAUAAUUAAAUAUAGAAUCUUUAUGA